CGAAGUGCUGGGAAGCCACCGCGCCUGGCCCAAGUUUGUAAUUUUAAAGUAACUUAAUUUUCCGCACUUGUUAGUGGGAUUGUGCAAUGCACGAGUUAUUCCAAGAUCCCCUGAAUUUGAGGAUAUGUAGCCUGAGGCGGUGUGCCUGCAGAGGGGCUGCUGCAGACCUUUGAGGGGAGCUGUUUUCUGUUCCAGCAGCCCUAGCUUUGGGGUGUGUUUUAACUGGGGCACCUGUCAGCUAGGGUCAGGAAUCCCCUGGGAUGUCAGUAAUGCCUCUGGUCAUACCUUUUAGAUGAAGCCACAUGUGGACAGUCUCCAGUUCUCACACCCUUCCCACUUGUCACCAGAGAGAGGACUCAGGACCCGGUGGGCUGACAGCGUUAGGACGAAUCCACACAUAUGGGUGGCUCAUACUUUCGGUGCCUGGUUAACCUGCCAGGUGACCCUGUCACAUGCCAUAUUGUUGCUUUUGAACCUGUACAUAUGCCUUAGUGGACUGCUGAGUAAGCAGGCUUUAGACAUUUGGGUUUGGCUAUUAAACAUUUAUACCAGGUGGUCAGCUGGAUGUGUUCUUGGCAGUGUUUGGGAAGUCAGAGUGCUUGGUCAAUGGAAGUCGUUUGGCUUAUUUAUAGAACAAUGGAUUUUGGCGAAAGUUUUAACCCCAGGAUCUGAGUUACACUGCAAAGCCAGUCCAUUAGCCACCUUUAGGCAGGCAUCAAAAAGGAGUAUUUUGGGCCGGGUGUGGUGGCUCACGCCUGUAAUCCCAGCACUUUGGGAAGCUGAGGUGGGCGGGUCGCUUGAGGUCAGGAGACCAGCCUGGCCAAAGUGGCGAAACCCCAUCUCUACUAAAAAUACAAAAAUUGGCCAGGCGUGGUGGUGGCUGCCUGUAAUUCCAGCUACUUGGGAGGCUGAGGCACGAGAAUUGCUUGAACCUGGGAGGCGGAGGUUGCAGUGAGCCAAGAUCACACCACUGCACUGCAGCCUGGGCGAUGGAGUGAGACUCUGUCUCAAAAAAUAAAUAAAUAAGAAGUACUUUGAAACUAUCUGUUCUCUGAUCUGAGACCUUGUCAAACAACUUUGUGCUUUCCAAAGAUAGAUUAAGACAAAUUUUGGUGUGGUUGUCACCAAGUAAUUCCAGAGGUGGAGGGUGGAAGGCUGUCUCCUCACUCAGCAUUCUACCCUCCAGGCCUCACCUCGCGCUGGGCAUACAGUCAUGCUGGAUACGGGAUUGCGGGCGGCUGUGGCUCUGACACCCUGGGGUUGGAGCCCCCAGACAGCCGUCCCAGACAGCCACCCAUCAGGGUACACGUCCAGUUACUUGAGUGGGGUUAGGCACAGCUGAUUUUUUUUUUUCCCAUCAGCAUUGGCUCCUAGCCUACACUGUGGUCCUUUCAGACGACCCCACGGAGGAAAGGCGAGGUGGUCACGUUAGCCGGAGUAAGGCAGUUUGAAAGAAGCGUGGGUCUGAGCAGAAUGGCAGUUAGAGUCAAAGAUGGCUGAUCUGAAGACUAUGAGAUGGAUCGGUCAUCCCCACCAUAGUUUUGUUUGGGCAGCCAGUUACACAUAAAUCGAGGAACUAGGUCUUCAUCUUGACCUCUGUGUGUCGUGUAUAUUCUAGUAUGAGUAUCGUUAAGACCAUUCCUACUGUUGUCACUUUGGUAUCCUCCAGGUGGGGUUCACCUUGCUUUGAGCUUGGCUUUUGGGUUCUUGUUUUUCUACCGGGGACUUUCUGUGCUUUCAGAUGUUUGAGACCAGGAAGGGGGGAAGGCUGUGCUUCAGUGGAGUGCCUGUGGGCUAGAAGCGUGGUGUGGGCCUGCCUGCCCCGACCCUGCUGUGACAGUUGGAGGGCGGGUGCUCACUGCAGGGCCCUGCCAGGUUGUCGUGUUCCAAAAUUGCCCCUUCAAAGGGGGCAGUAUUUUGGGGCUAUUUCUUGAAUGCCCAGGCUUUGGAAAGUGGGACCCCAAAAAGAACAAUCUGUCUUCAGUCUGAGAUUGCCAGAUCCGCAAGGCCCUUCAGGAGGGCAGGUUGGGAAGGUGACACAGCCCACACACACCUGUGGAGCGCACACCUUGGCAGCCUGUUGUGUGACCUGGCCCCGGCCCUGUGCCGCCCUCCGCAUCCGUGUCCAUGUGGUGUGGCCAUAAACCAGAAGUUCUUUCACUUAUGCUGGCAGAGUACCACUGGAAAUAAACUUGGUAACAUUUGAAAACAGCCAGUGUCCUUAAUGUGGACCAUGAGUUCCCAGCCCCAGAACCACAGGGGUGUCUGGCGGAAGAGGACUGUUCAGCUGGGCUAGGCUAGAGGGAGAGGCCUGCUGUGUUCACCCCGCAGGCGGCCCAUGCAGAGAGGCAGUGAGAGCCCAGCUGGUCCUGCCUCUGUUCUCACCUGUAGUGUGUUCUGGAGGUUAGUGGCAGGACUGGAUUACCUGGCUGGUGGGCUGGACAGAUGAAUCUGUUGGCAUCUGUACUUGAUCCCAUCGCACCAUCAGCUUGUCAGGGCCUCCAUUUGUCCACCUGUUACCUGGAUGGACUGACUUCAUAAUGUGCACAAGCAUCUUUUGGGAGCUAACUGCUUCAUCUCUGAAGCACACGUUUUUCCCCUCACUGACUGAUUUCUCAAGAGGCAGCCUGCAGGGUGCCUGGUAUGCAAUAGGGCCCCAAGAUGCUGACCAGCCAUGAGAGGAGAGCGACCACCUGUUCUUCCUGUAGCUUCUGGGGUCUCCUCACUGCAGUGUUAGGGCUGUAGCCUCUGUUGACCUUGGACUCUCCUUAACUCAAGCAUCUGUAAUGAGAAGUCGUGGUACUGCUGACCGCUGCCCUGCGAGUUGACCUUUGUCCUGCUGCUCAAGGCGUCUCCCUGUUUUUUUUGUUGACAAGACAAUCCUUAAUGGGAGUUGCCAGCAUCCAGGCUGGUAAUUCAGAAUUACCCUCCUGUGCCAGGACAGGGCCACACUCUGGUUAGGUUCGCUUAACUCACCAUCUGCUUUUUUUUUUUUUUUUUUUUUUUAAGACAAAGUAUCAUUCUGUUGCCUAGGCUGGGGUGCAGUGGCGCGAUCUCAGCUCACUGCAACCCCUGCCUUCUGGGUUCAAGCAGUUCUUCCGCAUCAACCUCCUGAGUAGCUGGGGUUAGAGGCGCACACCAGCAUGCCUGGCUAAUUUUUUUUGUAUUUAUAGUAGGGACGGGGUUUCACCAUGUGGGCCAGGCUGGUCUCGAAUGCCUGACCUCAAGCGAUCCAUCAGCCUCAGCCUCCCAAAGUGCUGGGAUUACAGGCGUGAACCACCACACCCGGCCACCAUCUGCUUUUGGCUGCUGAACUUGAGGGACGUAAUUUUGUUUUUGUAGGACUAACAUUAACUGAUACCCAAACACGGACUGAGGAAAGCCCUGUCUCACAGCAGACCAGGAUUGUUGAGCUGCAGGGAAGAGUUGAAUUUGUUUUGUUGACAGAAUGUCUUUUGUAUAAACAGACAACCCAGACAACCUGGUGAUCUGCGUGUCACCAGGUUUUGGUUUGUUUUGAAUCUGACACCCAGGGCUCAGGGUCUUUCAAAUUCUCAUUCCCCUUCUAGUAGUGCUUCUCGGAUUUAACCUGUGGUGAAGAACCAGGCUUGUAAUUUUCAACCUGUUGCAUGCCAAAACUUGUGUAUAAGGUCAAAAUGCUGCAGCGAUGCCAGAUUGCAGCCACAGUUACUGAGCGCCUCUGUGCUGCCUUGUGCACUGAUGGCAGCUUGAGGAUCUGACUUUCAGCAGCAUGGCUGGUAGAGUGUGGGGGUGCCCCCGGUGGGCGAGGUGGGACAGGGCUGCAGGCCAGGGGGUCUGAGCAGUGCUCAGCGACCUUGAGGCAGGUGGUGCCUUUGGAAUGCACAGACCUUGGUGUUCUGCUUCUUGAUGCUUCUGCCCAGCAGGUGACGAGGUCCCUGCUGCAGGCCCCAGAGAGUUGCCAUCCUCACAUCUGUGUACAGGACCUGCAUCCAGCUACUCCCCUGUAGAGACUCGGGGCGACCUUGGUGUCGGUUCCACAGGAGGGCUGGCUCUGUGUGCUUGCACAUCUGUGUGCUUGCACAGCGAGAGGUCCCGGCCCCAUGAUAGGGUGUGAUUCGUGUUGUGUGCCAGAGCGGCUGGUGAUGACUUUUGCCCCACGACAGUCAGUGCUGCAGGUGUGACUGGCAGACAUUAGCUUUAUCAGCUACAGAGAAGUGGAGUGAGAGAUGCUAGUCAGCAGACUGUGUGGCCCCAAGCCAUCGGCCCCAGGCCAUGGGGUCACUGGGCUGCCAGCUGGCGAGGGUGGCGGUACUGUCCGAGGCUGCACUGCGCCUGCUUGGGGGUGCAGGGAGCUGCUGACAUAACUAGUGGGAUGAGUCACCCUCCCUCCCGGCUGGCGAGUUGAGUUCAGAGUCCAGGUCCUUAGAGGAACUCAGAGUGGUUUUUCAUUUACACAGUACAUUUUUCGAUGAAGUCAUUUCUCUUGUAAUUGGAUAGACUGUCCCAACUGUAGGCAGGAAGAACAAAAUUUGUUACCUCGAGUACUCUGAAGAGUCUCUGUUGAUAGUAAGUGACGUUCUUAAAUCUAGAAUGGUCACUGGCGGUGACCCGGUGGUGGCGAUUCCUGUGGAACGCAGCAGUGGCAAGGGGUUUGGGGCCCAGGCUGGAAGUGGCACAUCUCAUGCCGCCAUCUGGGCAGACGAGGGGCUUCCUGGGUGUUCAGUGGACGUGUGGAUAUCAGCAGACUGCUCUAGUGCUCACUUGACCUUACUCUGCUUUUCAUCAGGGAACCUUAUCUUAAAGAGCAGUAAAAGAAACUGUUAACCCAUUCAUCUCCACAACUCUCAUGAAACAGACGUCAGACCUCACCACUGAUCUCCAUUGACAAGAGAAACCGAGUCACUAAGAACUAGCCAAGUUGCUUUGCCCAGCACCACAGUCUCUCAGGGAAGGAAGUCUCCCAGGGCUUUGUCUGGGCUGCUGAAGCUAGUGUGAAUUCUUUUCCACAUAGCCACGCUGUUGGGAAGGAUCCAGUGUCCUUUUUUUUUUUUUUUUUUUUUUGAGACGGUGUCUCGCUCUGUCACCCAGGCUGGAGUGCAGUGGCGCGAUCUCGGCUCACUGCAAGCUCCGCCUCCCAGGUUCACGCCAUUCUCCUGCCUCAGGCUCCCAAGUAGCUGGGACCACAGGUACCCACCACCAUGCCCAGCUAAUUUUUUGUAUUUUUAGUAGAGAUGGGGUUUCACCGUGUUAGCCAGGAUGGUCUCAAUCUCCUGACCUUGUGAUCCGCCCGCCUUGGCCUCCCAAAGUGCUGGGAUUACAGGCGUGAGCCACCGCGCCCGGCCGAUUCCAGUGUCUUAUACUCUGAAGGGACUCGUGAGGGAAGAGGAGAGAGCUGGGUACGGACAUUGCUGCAGGAGAAGAGGUUGCCAUCAAGCUUGAAUGUGUCAAAACCAAACACCCUCAGCUCCACAUUGAGAGCAAAAUCUACAAGAUGAUGCAGGGAGGAGUGGGCAUCCCCACCAUCAGAUGGUGCGGGGCAGAGGGGGACUACAACGUCAUGGUGAUGGAGCUGCUGGGGCCAAGCCUGGAGGACCUCUUCAACUUCUGCUCCAGGAAAUUCAGCCUCAAAACCGUCCUGCUGCUUGCUGACCAAAUGAUCAGUCGCAUCGAAUACAUUCAUUCAAAGAACUUCAUCCACCGGGAUGUGAAGCCAGACAACUUCCUCAUGGGCCUGGGGAAGAAGGGCAACCUGGUGUACAUCAUCGACUUCGGGCUGGCCAAGAAGUACCGGGAUGCACGCACCCACCAGCACAUCCCCUAUCGUGAGAACAAGAACCUCACGGGGACGGCGCGGUACGCCUCCAUCAACACGCACCUUGGAAUUGAACAAUCCCGAAGAGAUGACUUGGAGUCUCUGGGCUACGUGCUAAUGUACUUCAACCUGGGCUCUCUCCCCUGGCAGGGGCUGAAGGCUGCCACCAAGAGACAGAAAUACGAAAGGAUUAGCGAGAAGAAAAUGUCCACCCCCAUCGAAGUGUUGUGUAAAGGCUACCCUUCCGAAUUUGCCACAUACCUGAAUUUCUGCCGUUCCUUGCGUUUUGACGACAAGCCUGACUACUCGUACCUGCGGCAGCUUUUCCGGAAUCUGUUCCAUCGCCAGGGCUUCUCCUAUGACUACGUGUUCGACUGGAACAUGCUCAAAUUUGGUGCCAGCCGGGCCGCCGAUGACGCCGAGCGGGAGCGCAGGGACCGAGAGGAGCGGCUGAGACACUCGCGGAACCCGGCUACCCGCGGCCUCCCUUCCACAGCCUCCGGCCGCCUGCGGGGGACGCAGGAAGUGGCUCCCCCCACACCCCUCACCCCUACCUCACACACGGCUAACACCUCCCCCCGGCCCGUCUCCGGCAUGGAGAGAGAGCGGAAAGUGAGUAUGCGGCUGCACCGCGGGGCCCCCGUCAACAUCUCCUCGUCCGACCUCACAGGCCGACAAGAUACCUCUCGCAUGUCCACCUCACAGGUAGGUGCAGAGCUCCCGGGCGGGCGCUGGGCCUCGGGCUACCCCGUCCGAGUCAAGAGCGGGCUGUGGUUUCUCCAGGGCUUCUUCUUUCCUUUCUUCCCCCCAUUUUUGAGAGUUUUUAAUCUCGCCAGGGUGUGGCGUCUUGGUUGCAGAUGAGGCUUCUCGGGAGGGCCUGGGAGACAUGCUGGGCCGUCAUGGGGCUUGUCUCCUGGUUGCAGGUGGCCAGUCUCAGGUCUCAGGUCCCUGAGGCCAGCAAACCGUGGGGGCUUUCUCCUGCUGUUUGAGUGCCCCGCUGCCCGCAGCCGUCCCCAGGCAGCUGACACCGCUCGCCUGCUUGCGCCCCAUUGUGGGUGCCCCCAGCCCGAGGGAGCCUUCCUCAUUCUUCCUCAUUCUUGCCACUGGCCAGGGAUGGAGGCCCGUAGGGACCUCCACGGGCUUCUUGUGAGACCCUCCCUGGUGGCAUGCCCUGCAACGAGGCUUUCCUUCUUUUGACGGCCUCACCUGUCUUCCCUUGGACGAGAAGUACCCUGUUGCGCAGCCCAGGCCUAGCCACGGCCACCGCCUCUUCAGCAUCCUGCAGCGGUCUCUCCUCUCCUCGCUCUGGCUUUUGUUGUCUUUUGCGUUUGCUAACGUGCUCUUUGAACUAGAACAGCUUUCUCCAUAUGGAUCCAUUAUAUUUCUUCAAAUAGUUUUCUGGGUUGUUCGCCAACAGGGGCAGGGUUAGUGGGGCAGGGCUGUUUCACCAGCAGGCAUCCUGGGGGGUGCCCAGAUCCCCCACGGGUCUUCCGGAUGAGCAGGAACUCAGUUCAGAAAUGCCCUGGAGCCUGGCUCUGGGCUUGUGGGGAGGUGUUUGUUGGGAUCACAGGAUGGAGCCAGGCCUGCUGCCGUGAGCGGGGCUGGGUGUAGCUGGCUAGCCAGGAACAUGCCGGAGUGGGGAGCACUCUUGACCACUUGCCGUCUUUUAAUGAUUGGGGUUUUACUGCACGUUUCUAAUUCACUAAUAAUUUCACUAGAAACAGACCUUUUUGUAUAACUUCUUCCCAAAGAGACCAAAGAUGCAGGGAUUUUGGCUUCGUGGUUAUUUUGACUUUGUGGUUAUAUGAAUUGGGCUCGAGGGGUCUGGGCUGCGUCACGAGAAUGGGUCCCUUACGUGCACACAACCCUGCUGUCACCUCCAGACACAGCACAGAAAGGGUUUAACUGGCUUCUUUCCACGAGCCUGGCACUUGCGCAUCAGUUCCUGUGAGCAGUUCCCGGGAGGGUCUGCCCGUGCCCUCGUGUCUUGAUGUGCGGCUGGCUCUGUAGCCCCUGAACCAUGGUACAGGAGCCCAGAGUGCUCCCCAUGCUGGGUGCUGACCGGACUUGGACAGCCUCGCCCCAGCGCUUGGCUGACAAAGACUAGGGAAGGGGCCUGAGUGCUUUUUGUUUCUUUUAAAGAAAGUAAAGUGUCCAGUGGUUUGGGAUCUUUGUGGGCAGUGAAGGUGUCCUGAGCGUGCUGAGUAGCCACAGCCCUGAGUCCAGCUGCCUUUUCUCGGUACACGGCCUUGGCGGCACCUGGGUGUGGCUGUUGUAGCCACCAGCCCCCAAGGUGGCCGUGAGCAGUGUCUCCUUCCAUGGUGAGCUGUGGCAGGAACCCGCAGCUGGCUCUUAGGCCCUCGUUUUCCAUAUGAGGAAAUACAACGUGGGCUCUAACAGCAGGGAGGAGUCUCCAGAGAGAGCUGGUUUGGGGGUGUGUUCUCUCCAAAAGAAGCCUCUUGGCCUCUGCUCCUGGACACCCUGGGGGGCCUUCCUGAGAGGCAUGUUGAGGGCUCCCCACCUCCAGGGCGGGCCCCCUCCUUUGUCACCAUCUCACAGGAAGGCUUUGGCCGUGUGUCCUUCCUGCCAGACUCUGCCAGCACCAGCACACGUGGUGGCUGUGAGCAGCAGCUCCCGUUUUGAAUCCCAAGGGGGAAUACAGGAGGCUCAAUUGCUCUGAGCGCCUCACCUGUUUGCUCGGGUGAGCUGGAGACACAGUCACCGUGGGCAGUGACUCAUCCCCGGCCAGUCUUCCUCCUCGGGCCGUCGCUCUUCCCUGUUCUUUCUGCUCCUCUCAGGAGACCUUGCGCCCUGUGGAGAUGGGAGGAGGCAGCAGGAAGGUCUCCCAGGGCUUGCUGGCCGUGGCUGGGUGUGGAUGGGUGGAAGACCACGUGGCAGCCUGCCUGUAGGUCACAGAGGCCCCCAUAGUUGUAGGGCCCCGCCCCAGCCCGGACUCCGCCUGGGUCUGUUCCCUCUUCGCCCCCUCUCUUUUCGGGCUGUUGGUGUUCGGCCAGGGCUCUUUGGCUACAGUAGCCUGGGCCCUAAAGGCCAUCUAGUUGCUGAGUCUGUUUGGGGUUUUUACUUGGUGAGAAGAAGGCCUUGUCAUUC